CACCGGCAGCACCAUGUCGCUCACGGUCGUCAGCAUGGCGUGUGUUGGGUUCUUCUUGCUGCAGGGGGCCUGGCCACAUGAGGGAGUCCACAGAAAACCUUCCCUCCUGGCCCACCCAGGUCGCCUGGUGAAAUCAGAAGAGACAGUCAUCCUGCAAUGUUGGUCAGAUGUCAUGUUUGAACACUUCCUUCUGCACAGAGAGGGGAUGUUUAACGACACUUUGCGCCUCAUUGGAGAACACCAUGAUGGGGUCUCCAAGGCCAACUUCUCCAUCAGUCGCAUGAAGCAAGACCUGGCAGGGACCUACAGAUGCUACGGUUCUGUUACUCACUCCCCCUAUCAGUUGUCAGCUCCCAGUGACCCUCUGGACAUCGUGAUCAUAGGUCUAUAUGAGAAACCUUCUCUCUCAGCCCAGCCGGGCCCCACGGUUCUGGCAGGAGAGAAUGUGACCUUGUCCUGCAGCUCCCGGAGCUCCUAUGACAUGUACCAUCUAUCCAGGGAAGGGGAGGCCCAUGAACGUAGGCUCCCUGCAGGGACCAAGGUCAACGGAACAUUCCAGGCCAACUUUCCUCUGGGCCCUGCCACCCAUGGAGGGACCUACAGAUGCUUCGGCUCUUUCCGUGACUCUCCAUACGAGUGGUCAAAGUCAAGUGACCCACUGCUUGUUUCUGUCACAGGAAACCCUUCAAAUAGUUGGCCUUCACCCACUGAACCAAGCUCCGAAACCGGUAACCCCAGACACCUACAUAUUCUGAUUGGGACCUCAGUGGUCAAAAUCCCUUUCACCAUCCUCCUCUUCUUUCUCCUUCAUCGCUGGUGCUCCGACAAAAAAAAUGCUGCUGUAAUGGACCAAGAGCCUGCAGGGAACAGAACAGUGAACAGCGAGGAUUCUGAUGAACAAGACCAUCAGGAGGUGUCAUACGCAUAAUUGGAUCACUGUGUUUUCACACAGAGAAAAAUCACUCGCCCUUCUGAGAGGCCCAAGACACCCCCAACAGAUACCAGCAUGUACAUAGAACUUCCAAAUGCUGAGCCCAGAUCCAAAGUUGUCUUCUGUCCACGAGCACCACAGUCAGGCCUUGAGGGGAUCUUCUAGGGAGA